AUUCCGCGGCCGCCGCCAGCUGAGGGGAGCGUCGCGGGCCGAGGAGCAGAUGCCGCGGGGGCCGCUCGCAGCCGCCGCUGACUUGUGAAUGGGACCGGGACUGGGGCCGGGACUGACACCGCAGCGCUUGCCCUGCGCCAGGGACUGGCGGCUCGGAGGUUGCGUCCACCCUCAAGGGCCCCAGAAAUCACUGUGUUUUCAGCUCAGCGGCCCUGUGACAUUCCUUCGUGUUGUCAUUUGUUGAGUGACCAAUCAGAUGGGUGGAGUGUGUUACAGAAAUUGGCAGCAAGUAUCCAAUGGGUGAAGAAGAAGCUAACUGGGGACGUGGGCAGCCCUGACGUGAUGAGCUCAACCAGCAGAGACAUUCCAUCCCAAGAGAGGUCUGCGUGACGCGUCCGGGAGGCCACCCUCAGCAAGACCACCGUACAGUUGGUGGAAGGGGUGACAGCUGCAUUCUCCUGUGCCUACCACGUAACCAAAAAUGAAGGAGAACUACUGUUUACAAGCCGCCCUGGUGUGCCUGGGCAUGCUGUGCCACAGCCAUGCCUUUGCCCCAGAGCGGCGGGGGCACCUGCGGCCCUCCUUCCAUGGGCACCAUGAGAAGGGCAAGGAGGGGCAGGUGCUACAGCGCUCCAAGCGUGGCUGGGUCUGGAACCAGUUCUUCGUGAUAGAGGAGUACACCGGGCCUGACCCCGUGCUUGUGGGCAGGCUUCAUUCAGAUAUUGACUCUGGUGAUGGGAACAUUAAAUACAUUCUCUCAGGGGAAGGAGCUGGAACCAUUUUUGUGAUUGAUGACAAAUCAGGGAACAUUCAUGCCACCAAGACGUUGGAUCGAGAAGAGAGAGCCCAGUACACGUUGAUGGCUCAGGCGGUGGACAGGGACACCAAUCGGCCACUGGAGCCACCGUCGGAAUUCAUUGUCAAGGUCCAGGACAUUAAUGACAACCCUCCGGAGUUCCUGCACGAGACCUAUCAUGCCAACGUGCCUGAGAGGUCCAAUGUGGGAACGUCAGUAAUCCAGGUGACAGCUUCAGAUGCAGAUGACCCCACUUAUGGAAAUAGCGCCAAGUUAGUGUACAGUAUCCUCGAAGGACAACCCUAUUUUUCGGUGGAAGCACAGACAGGUAUCAUCAGAACAGCCCUACCCAACAUGGACAGGGAGGCCAAGGAGGAGUACCACGUGGUGAUCCAGGCCAAGGACAUGGGUGGACAUAUGGGCGGACUCUCAGGGACAACCAAAGUGACGAUCACACUGACCGAUGUCAAUGACAACCCACCAAAGUUUCCGCAGAGCGUAUACCAGAUGUCUGUGUCAGAAGCAGCCGUCCCUGGGGAGGAAGUAGGAAGAGUGAAAGCUAAAGAUCCAGACAUUGGAGAAAAUGGCUUAGUCACAUACAAUAUUGUUGAUGGAGAUGGUAUGGAAUCGUUUGAAAUCACAACGGACUAUGAAACACAGGAGGGGGUGAUAAAGCUGAAAAAGCCUGUAGAUUUUGAAACCAAAAGAGCCUAUAGCUUGAAGGUAGAGGCAGCCAACGUGCACAUCGACCCGAAGUUUAUCAGCAAUGGCCCUUUCAAGGACACUGUGACCGUCAAGAUCUCAGUAGAAGAUGCUGAUGAGCCCCCUAUGUUCUUGGCCCCAAGUUACAUCCACGAAGUCCAAGAAAAUGCAGCUGCUGGCACCGUGGUUGGGAGAGUGCAUGCCAAAGACCCUGAUGCUGCCAACAGCCCGAUAAGGUAUUCCAUCGAUCGUCACACUGACCUCGACAGAUUUUUCACUAUUAAUCCAGAGGAUGGUUUUAUUAAAACUACAAAACCUCUGGAUAGAGAGGAAACAGCCUGGCUCAACAUCACUGUCUUUGCAGCAGAAAUCCACAAUCGGCAUCAGGAAGCCAAAGUCCCAGUGGCCAUUAGGGUCCUUGAUGUCAACGAUAAUGCUCCCAAGUUUGCUGCCCCUUAUGAAGGUUUCAUCUGUGAGAGUGAUCAGACCAAGCCACUUUCCAACCAGCCAAUUGUUACAAUUAGUGCAGAUGACAAGGAUGACACGGCCAAUGGACCAAGAUUUAUCUUCAGCCUACCCCCUGAAAUCAUUCACAAUCCAAAUUUCACAGUCAGAGACAACCGAGAUAACACAGCAGGCGUGUACGCCCGGCGUGGAGGGUUCAGUCGGCAGAAGCAGGACUUGUACCUUCUGCCCAUAGUGAUCAGCGAUGGCGGCAUCCCGCCCAUGAGUAGCACCAACACCCUCACCAUCAAAGUCUGCGGGUGCGACGUGAACGGGGCACUGCUCUCCUGCAACGCAGAGGCCUACAUUCUGAACGCCGGCCUGAGCACAGGCGCCCUGAUCGCCAUCCUCGCCUGCAUCGUCAUUCUCCUGGGUUGCCCAAGCUUAAUGGAACCCCCCUCUCCCAGGGAAGACAUGAGAUUGCUUUAUCUGGGCUUCCAGCUGAUGCUAUUUUCCUAUGUUAAAGUAAACAGAAGAUUUUGUCUUCUGGGGGUCUUUAUAAAACUUCCUUUCCUCUAUGUGGUGGCUACAGAGAGUCCAACCACACUUACGUCAUUGUAGUAUUGUUUGUGACCCUGAGAAGGCAAAAGAAAGAACCACUCAUUGUCUUUGAGGAAGAAGAUGUCCGUGAGAACAUCAUUACUUAUGAUGAUGAAGGGGGUGGGGAAGAAGACACAGAAGCCUUUGAUAUUGCCACCCUCCAGAAUCCUGAUGGUAUCAAUGGAUUUAUCCCCCGCAAAGACAUCAAACCUGAGUAUCAGUACAUGCCUAGACCUGGGCUCCGGCCAGCGCCCAACAGCGUGGAUGUCGAUGACUUCAUCAACACGAGAAUACAGGAGGCAGACAAUGACCCCACGGCUCCUCCUUAUGACUCCAUUCAAAUCUACGGUUAUGAAGGCAGGGGCUCAGUGGCCGGGUCCCUGAGCUCCCUAGAGUCGGCCACCACAGAUUCAGACUUGGACUAUGAUUAUCUACAGAACUGGGGACCUCGUUUUAAGAAACUAGCAGAUUUGUAUGGUUCCAAAGACACUUUUGAUGACGAUUCUUAACAAUAACGAUACAAAUUUGGCCUUAAGAACUGUGUCUGGCGUUCUCAAGAAUCUAGAAGAUGUGUAAACAGGUAUUUUUUUAAAUCAAGGAAAGGCUCAUUUAAAACAGGCAAAGUUUUACAGAGAGGAUACAUUUAAUAAAACUGCGAGGACAUCAAAGUGGUAAAUACUGUGAAAUACCUUUUCUCACAAAAAGGCAAAUAUUGAAGUUGUUUAUCAACUUCGCUAGAAAAAAAAAACACUUGGCAUACAAAAUAUUUAAGUGAAGGAGAAGUCUAACGCUGAACUGACAAUGAAGGGAAAUUGUUUAUGUGUUAUGAACAUCCAAGUCUUUCUUCUUUUUUAAGUUGUCAAAGAAGCUUCCACAAAAUUAGAAAGGACAACAGUUCUGAGCUGUAAUUUCGCCUUAAACUCUGGACACUCUAUAUGUAGUGCAUUUUUAAACUUGAAAUAUAUAAUAUUCAGCCAGCUUAAACCCAUACAAUGUAUGUACAAUACAAUGUACAAUUAUGUCUCUUGAGCAUCAAUCUUGUUACUGCUGAUUCUUGUAAAUCUUUUUGCUUCUACUUUCAUCUUAAACUAAUACGUGCCAGAUAUAACUGUCUUGUUUCAGUGAGAGACGCCCUAUUUCUAUGUCAUUUUUAAUGUAUCUAUUUGUACAAUUUUAAAGUUCUUAUUUUAGUAUACGUAUAAAUAUCAGUAUUCUGACAUGUAAGAAAAUGUUACGGCAUCACACUUAUAUUUUAUGAACAUUGUACUGUUGCUUUAAUAUGAGCUUCAAUAUAAGAAGCAAUCUUUGAAAUAAAAAAAGAUUUUUUUUUAAUUCUGGGUUUGAUUCUUAACAUUGAAACAAACGUUAAGUAUUUCUAAUGAUCCAUUUAUAUUUCUAAUUUAAUUGUGAUCUUUUAAUAACCCUAUUUAUGAUCUGUUGUUGUCUGUCUGCUGCUUUUAUUGUUUAUUUAAAAUCAAAUAUGUUUUACAAAUGUUUUUUCAGACAAGAUUCUGUAACAUCAUGUAAAGCUUUUUUGUACAUUCUUGGUGUUAACCUCCUGGCUUCUCUUCACACACAUCUUCUAAAAAAGAAGGAUGUGAAAGAACUAGGUCAGUCUAUGACUUUGCAAUAUGUGUUAUAUAGUAUGCAUUUAUCUUGUAUAUCAGUAAUUUGAUGGUUAUGAGAGAUGAAUCCAUGAGGGAAUGGAGCUAUCAGAACUCUAAUGUUCCAGGUAUACAUUCUAUGCCCCACACUGAGCACUGGGGAACUGGGGGACUAGAGUCAAAAAUAUAAAUUUGCCCAGACUCUAAUGUUAUUCUAUUUUUUCUUCUGUUGAACUUACCAGGCUAUUGUAAGACUCUUGAUAGUUGAAACUGCUUAUUUUUCCUCCUGUAAUUUUAACUAAUUGUAAAAUGAUGUGGCAUUUUAUGUUUUAAUGAGAAUGGGCGAUUCAUUUAAAAAAGCUUUGUUUAGAAUAUGCUUGGGGCCGUAAGCUCAGAAUGAGGGCAGGGACCAUUUUGGAUUCUGAGAGUCGAUGCCAUUUGGUCCAGGAGUGUGUCUACAGUCCCCUGCAUUCCAGCUAGUUUCUUGGGGAUUGAAACUUAUGUGAAGGGCAUUUCACCUGUUCAGUUGGGCCAAAGGUCAAAACGUAGCAAUACUUGGGGAAAGACCACAUAAAGUCACACUGCAAGUGCUUUCCCUCUUUCCCCCUACACACAGGGCACGUGCUUUUUCUUGGAUUGCAGACAAUUUUUACAGUUUUUUUCUGACUUUAUUGUGAAAGUUUGUUUCAAGCAUUUCUUGAUAUCAUGUUAUGUACUAUUUUUAUGAUUUAGUCAACAUGCAUACAAAGAAAUGUUUUUUAUGAAGUGCUCACUUCCAUUUUACUUUGCAUUGAAAUCAAAUUGGGCUGAACACUUCAAUGGAAUACAUUUUGUGGACAAUGUCACUUUAGAAUCUUUCAUCUCAGUGAAGGAUUACACAUUCUCAAUACUUCCAUAAUUGCAGGUUGUGUUCAUUUUUUUAUAUAGUUUUUGUAAUCCAAAGAAUAUUUUGCUAGAUUUGCACAGAUCUCCAAUUGAAUUUGCAAUGAAGAAAUAACUCAAAAGGAAUAUGAAUAGCAUUUAAAUAAGUAUACAGCUGUAAGUAACCCUGUCACCAUGGAUGAUCCUUUUCUCUAGGAAUGUAUUUGGAUUAGAGAUGACAACUACAUUUUCGCAUUUUUAUGUUGAAGUCUUUUUUAAAAAGGCUGUUUACUUUUCAGUAGUUAAGAAUACUUGUUUUUCUUUUUCUUUUUUUUUUUUUUUUUUACCUUUUAUUUUUUCGUUAAGCCUCUAUUGUUUGUAGAACACUCUUAGAAACUUGGAAAUAAAAUGUCUUUCCCAACUAGUGGAGUCCUUUUUCAUUUGGAGCACAUUGCCUUAAAAGAAGUCUUAAUUUAAACGGUCCUUCCUUAUUCUAAAGUAAUCACUGUUUUAUACCAUCUAUGCAGCUAAAAGAAGGAACAUGCUUCUGUUCUUUUCCUCAAGUAAUGGUUAUUGUUUCUAGUCAUCAUUCAUUCAUUGAUUCAUUCAUUAAUUCAUCAAAAUCUUAUUUUAUAAACCCUGUUCCACUUACUGGAGGAUUCAGAAUGAAUCUUACUACCUUUUCUGACAUCUUUUGAUAAUUCAGCCCUGUACCAAAGUAUCCACCUUGUUGUCUUAUAAUCACCUAUUUACCUAUUUGCCCUCCUAGAAAAUGCAAGAAGAUAUUUUCUCUCCUUCCAAAUUGAAGGAAGAACAUAAAAGAUAUAACAGGAAGGAGAUGGUGAGAUAUAGAGUGUGAGCGGAAAUUAGGCCAGCUGUGGCAAUUCUGGACAGAUCUUGGGUUUAGCUAAGUUAUUUCUUUUAGGCCUGGGUUUCUGGGGGUGACAGGGAAGAUAAAAGAGUAGUUUAUUUGCACCUCUUGGAGAAUUGCUUAAAAAUAUAGAGAUCAUGGCUCUGUAUGUCAGGUGGAACCAGGUCAGGAGUAUUUGAAACUGCUCCUGGGUCAUUGUGACAUAUCCUUCACAUCUUUUUGAGAAACUUUAUAAGACAAUGGGGGUGAAUGGGGGCUGGGCAGUUGGAGUCUCUGAGCAGAAGAGGGGCAAAAUUUAUUUGGCAGGCAGUGUGGAGGACAGAUUAGGAGCAUAUAAACCCAGAGGUGUGCCCCAGGAGGGCUUUUGCAAAGGUCAAUAUGAGAUAGAAUGAGGGCCUGAAAUAAUUCAGUAAUUUGGAGAUGGAGAAGAGGAAAGACUUCUCUGCUCUUGCACUGCCAUCAGCCUGGUCUGGGCCAUGGUCAUCUCUGACCCGGAAGACUGACCCCACCUCUUGGCUCACCCUCUGCCUCCCAACCUCCUCUUCACAAAGAAGCCAGAGGGAUACUUUUAACACACAACCCAGAUCACAUGACUUCGUAACUUAAACCUCUUCACUGGCUUCCCAAAGACUUAAAAUGAAUUCUGAUGCCUUUAUUUUAUUGCUUUACAUGAACAGGGCCCUGCGAACCUCUCCAGUGUCAUUCCACUCCAUCCUCCUUUCAGUGCACGAUGCUCCAGCCACACUGGCCAUCUUUCGGUUCCUGAUACAAAAAAAAACACGUUCCUUUUCCAUGGAAAGCAGGUCACCCUUGUUAUUUUGUAUCGAUGACAACUCUUUAAACUUAUUUUGCUUUUUGGCUUUAUGUAUGUGUGUGGGUGGGUGGGACUGACUGCCCCACUAGAAUGUAAGCUCCAUGAGGGCAGGGAAUCUUGCUUUCUUGUUUACCAUUGUAUACUCAGUUCUUUACACAGUGCCUGAAACAUAACAGGUACACAAUAAAUAUCUAUUGAAUGAAAGCAAA